CUCACUGCCGGCGGUCCCAACUCCAGGCACCAUGUUCCCCGCGGGCCCCCCCAGCCACAGCCUCCUCCGGCUCCCCCUGCUGCAGUUGCUGCUACUGGUGGUGCAGGCCGUGGGGAGGGGGCUGGGCCGCGCCAGCCCGGCCGGGGGCCCCCUGGAAGAUGUGGUCAUCGAGAGGUACCACAUCCCCAGGGCCUGUCCCCGGGAAGUGCAGAUGGGGGAUUUUGUGCGCUACCACUACAACGGCACUUUUGAAGAUGGCAAGAAGUUUGAUUCAAGCUAUGAUCGCAACACCUUGGUGGCCAUCGUGGUGGGUGUGGGGCGCCUCAUCACUGGCAUGGACCGAGGCCUCAUGGGCAUGUGUGUCAACGAGCGGCGACGCCUCAUUGUGCCUCCCCACCUGGGCUAUGGGAGCAUCGGCCUGGCGGGGCUCAUUCCACCGGAUGCCACCCUCUACUUCGAUGUGGUUCUGCUGGAUGUGUGGAACAAGGAAGACACCGUGCAGGUGAGCACAUUGCUGCGCCCGCCCCACUGCCCCCGCAUGGUCCAGGACGGCGACUUUGUCCGCUACCACUACAAUGGCACCCUGCUGGACGGCACCUCCUUCGACACCAGCUACAGUAAGGGCGGCACUUAUGACACCUACGUCGGCUCUGGUUGGCUGAUCAAGGGCAUGGACCAGGGGCUGCUGGGCAUGUGUCCUGGAGAGAGAAGGAAGAUUAUCAUCCCUCCAUUCCUGGCCUAUGGCGAGAAAGGCUAUGGGACAGUGAUCCCCCCACAGGCCUCGCUGGUCUUUCACGUCCUCCUGAUUGACGUGCACAACCCGAAGGACGCUGUCCAGCUAGAGACGCUGGAGCUCCCCCCCGGCUGUGUCCGCAGAGCCGGGGCCGGGGACUUCAUGCGCUACCACUACAAUGGCUCCUUGAUGGACGGCACCCUCUUCGAUUCCAGCUACUCCCGCAACCACACCUACAAUACCUAUAUCGGGCAGGGUUACAUCAUCCCCGGGAUGGACCAGGGGCUGCAGGGUGCCUGCAUGGGGGAACGCCGGAGAAUUACCAUCCCCCCGCACCUCGCCUAUGGGGAGAAUGGAACUGGAGACAAGAUCCCUGGCUCUGCCGUGCUAAUCUUCAACGUCCAUGUCAUUGACUUCCACAACCCUGCGGAUGUGGUGGAAAUCAGGACACUGUCCCGGCCAUCUGAGACCUGCAAUGAGACCACCAAGCUUGGGGACUUUGUUCGAUACCAUUACAACUGUUCUUUGCUGGACGGCACCCAGCUGUUCACCUCAGGGGAAACUGACGCAGGGAGCCAUGAGCCCUCGAGGCCACACUUUAGGGGGCAGAGGCAUGACUACGGGGCCCCCCAGGAGGCGACUCUCGGGGCCAACAAGGUGAUCGAAGGCCUGGACACGGGCCUGCAGGGCAUGUGUGUGGGAGAGAGGCGGCAGCUCAUCGUGCCCCCGCACCUGGCCCACGGGGAGAGUGGAGCCCGGGGAGUCCCAGGCAGUGCUGUGCUGCUGUUUGAGGUGGAGCUGGUGUCCCGGGAGGAUGGGCUGCCCACAGGCUACCUGUUUGUGUGGCACAAGGACCCUCCUGCCAACCUGUUUGAAGACAUGGACCUCAACAAGGAUGGCGAGGUCCCUCCGGAGGAGUUCUCCACCUUCAUCAAGGCUCAAGUGAGUGAGGGCAAAGGACGCCUCAUGCCUGGGCAGGACCCUGAGAAAACCAUAGGAGACAUGUUCCAGAACCAGGACCGCAACCAGGACGGCAAGAUCACAGUCGACGAGCUCAAGCUGAAGUCAGAUGAGGACGAGGAGCGGGUCCACGAGGAGCUCUGAGGGGCAGGGAGCCUGGCCAGGCCUGAGACACAGAGGCCCACUGCGAGGGGGACAGUGGCGGUGGGACUGACCUGCUGACAGUCACCCUCCCUCUGCUGGGAUGAGGUCCAGGAGCCAACUAAAACAAUGGCAGAGGAGACAUCUCUGGUGUUCCCACCACCCUAGAUGAAAAUCCACAGCACAGACCUCUACCGUGUUUCUCUUCCAUCCCUAAACCACUUCCUUAAAAUGUUUGGAUUUGCAAAGCCAAUUUGGGGCCUGUGGAGCCUGGGGUUGGAUAGGGCCAUGGCUGGUCCCCCACCAUACCUCCCCUCCACAUCACUGACACAGCUGAGCUUGUUAUCCAUCUCCCCAAACUUUCUCUUUCUUUGUACUUCUUGUCAUCCCCACUCCCAGCCCCUUUUCCUCUAUGUGACAGCUCCCUAGGACCCCUCUGCCUUCCUCCCCAAUCCUGACUGGCUCCUAGGGAAGGGGAAGGCUCCUGGAGGGCAGCCCUACCUCUCCCAUGCCCUUUGCCCUCCUCCCUCGCCUCCAGUGGAGGCUGAGCUGACCCUGGGCUGCUGGAGGCCAGACUGGGCUGUAGUUAGCUUUUCAUCCCUAAAGAAGGCUCCUUUCCCUAAGGAACCAUAGAAGAGAGGAAGAAAACAAAGGGCAUGUGUGAGGGAAGCUGCUUGGGUGGGUGUUAGGGCUAUGAAAUCUUGGAUUUGGGGCUGAGGGGUGGGAGGGAGGGCAGAGCUCUGCACACUCAAAGGCUAAACUGGUGUCAGUCCUUUUUUCCUUUGUUCCAAAUAAAAGAUUAAACCAA